ACCUGACUAGUUUUUCUCUUUUUUUAAGGAACACACAUUUUUAAGGAACAUCACAUGGCAUGAGCCAGUUUUACAACAGGGCUGUUUUCCUGCCACUGGUUCAGUAGCGUGUGUCCCCAGCUUCCCUCACACCGUUCAGUGUCAGUCCAAUCACAACAGCAGCAGUAGCAGCAACACACCUGAAACAAUCAACCUACCCCCAAAACUAAACACCAAAAAGUUUGGGGCCUUGGAGGUCUGGGGUUUAAGUGGGAGGUGUACCUCCUUCUCUCCUUCUGGGUUCAGAGCAGAGUUUUGCAAUUCCUGAUGAGUAAUGGAAAGGCUGGAGUGUGUGCUGUCUUUAAGAUGUGAUUUGAUUGUAAUAACAUUCAAAAUACCAUCAACUUUCAUGUAUAAUGCUAAAUACUGGGCACUUACUAUGUGCCAGGCACAUUUAAGGUUGACAACAGCCAGAGGCGGUCAAUAGCACGAUGGCUGUUUGCCUUUGACAGAGGAGGAGCACUGAGGCACAGGAAGGUGGGUACCGUUGGCCACGGGUCCCCUGCCUGGGAGGCUGGGCAGGUUGUCACACCAGGGAGUCUGGCGGGAUCCCUGGUUGGCGUCUCAUGCAUCAGCUUCCAUCAGAGCAUCCCUGCCGCCCUGGGUCCUGCUACCCCUAGUCCCUUCCUCUGCUCCUGCCUGGGGAGAUUCCCUAAGCAGUAACGUAAGAUCCUCCUUGCACGACUUGAUGGAAACAGGGAAAGUAUCCCCAUGCUGGGCCAGCAUAACGAUUUCUGAGCAUCCACGCUAUUUGAGGGUCUUUCAUGUCGGCUAUUCCAACUUCAUGACACUCCUGCGAGGAUGCGUGUAUCCUCCUCAUUCUGGAAGAUGAAGAAGUGUGCUCAGCUGUCUAAGGAGGCUGUGUGGGGCAUCAGAGACCAUGCAUUUCCUCAGGGGGUUGCAGAGUGUGCUGUGUGGUUUCACCUGGACCCUGAGCGUCCAGCCUACUCUUCCUAUGACUUUGGAUGAAUUCCUGAUUGAAUAGUCUACCUGGCCUGCUUGGAAAUCUGACCAGCCUCUCUCACUUUAAUACCCAUGUAGGUUGCUGUUGGGAAUUGCAUUUGUGCGGCCCACAGAGUGCCUGGUGAUGUGGUUGUACCUGCUGCUAUCAGUGGUCAAUUCUGUGUGCUGAGGCCCACAAAGAAGUCACAUUUCUUUCUCUGAAGAUGAUAAAAGCGGAGGCAUCUCUCAAUCUGGAAGGGGCUAGCUGGGCAUGAAGGUGGUGGCAGAGGCUCCCCUAGACCCCGAGUGACAGCCCGUGCUUCAAAGAGCAUGAAUAUACGGAGUUUGGGAAAUGGAUGGAUGGCUGGGAGACCAGGAGGAAAAGGAUUCCAGGUCACGACUGGUGUGUCCUCAGGCUGGGGAUCCAAGGAGUCAUCCGGGGCUUCGACGUGGACGUUUCUUACUUCACGGGAGAUUACGCUCCUCGAGUGUCCAUUCAAGCAGCAAACUUGGAAGAAGAUAAACUACCAGAAAUCCCAGAAAGAGGAACCAGGACAGGAGCUGCAGCCACUCCUGAGGAGUUUGAAGCCAUUGCUGAGCUAAAAUCCGACGACUGGAGUUACUUGGUUCCCAUGACUGAGCUUAAGCCAGGAAACCCUGCUUCCGGCCACAACUAUUUUCUUGUCAAUUCCCAGCAGAGAUGGACUCAUAUCAGACUCAACAUUUUCCCAGAUGGUGGAAUUGCACGACUUAGAGUAUUCGGUACUGGACAAAAAGACUGGACUGCAACUGACCCCAAAGAACCUGCAGACCUAGUGGCCAUCGCUUUUGGGGGUGUCUGUGUAGGAUUUAGUAAUGCUAAGUUUGGGCACCCAAACAAUAUAAUAGGAGUUGGCGGGGCAAAGUCUAUGGCGGAUGGUUGGGAAACUGCAAGAAGGCUGGACCGGCCACCAAUAUUAGAAAAUGAUGAGAAUGGCAUUCUCUUGGUUCCGGGUUGUGAAUGGGCAGUUUUCCGAUUGGCACAUCCUGGAGUAAUAACUCGAAUUGAAAUUGACACAAAAUAUUUUGAAGGCAAUGCUCCUGACAGCUGUAAAGUGGAUGGGUGCAUCCUGACAACUCAGGAAGAAGAAGCCGUGAUCAGGCAAAAGUGGAUUCUCCCGGCCCACAAGUGGAAACCACUGCUUCCAGUGACCAAGUUGUCUCCCAACCAAAGUCAUCUGUUCGAUAGCCUGACCCUAGAGCUCCAAGAUGUCAUCACUCACGCCAGGCUCACCAUCGUCCCCGACGGGGGAGUGAGCCGCCUUCGGCUCCGGGGCUUCCCCAGCUCCAUCUGCCUCCUGAGGCCCCGGGAGAAGCCCAUGUUGAAGUUCUCGGUGAGCUUCAAAGCAAACCCUUAACACACACAAAGCCCCGGUGUCGGACACACAGCAGUAAUUUCCCAGUCAUAGUCUUCUUUUCAAAUGUUUUGAACACCUGGUGAUUUAAUAAAGUGGUCGUCUCACAAA